CAUGGCCCUCUGGCACGGCCCUCUGGCACCUUACCCUUUGCCAGCUCCAUGCCCAGCCCUGUGGAUGCAUCCUCAGCAGACGGUGGCAGCGGGUUGGGUUCCCACCGGAGAAAGCGGACCACCUUCAGCAAAGGGCAGCUACUGGAGCUGGAGAGGGCGUUUGCAGCAUGGCCCUACCCCAACAUCAGCACCCAUGAGCACCUGGCCUGGGUCACUUGCCUUCCUGAGGCCAAGGUACAGGUGUGGUUCCAGAAGCGCUGGGCCAAAAUAAUCAAGAACAGGAAGUCAGGAAUUCUAAGCCCUGGGUCUGAGUGCCCCCAGAGCUCCUGUUCUCUUCCAGACACCCUCCAGCAGCCCUGGGAUCCCCAAAUGCCAGGCCAACCUCCACCCUCCAGCGGCACACCUCAGCGCACCUCAGUGUGUCGACAUAGCUCCUGUCCAGCUCCUGGCUUGAGUCCACGGCAGGGCUGGGAAGGGGCUAAAGCUGUAGCCCCAUGGGGAUCAGCUGGGGCUUCAGAGGUCCACCCUUCUUUAGAGCGAGCUACUCCCCAGACUUCACUAGGCAGCCUGUCUGACCUCAUCUAUGCCUUGGCCAUUGUCGUCAAUGUGGACCACUCCUAGUCUUUGUCCAGAACUUGCAAGGCCCCUCCUCUGACUCCUGUGGCCCACCCUGCCCCUCCUGGGAUUGAACACAUCAGAAGUGGAUUCCCUGGCCCCACUUUUUAUGCAAAGGGAUUCCCUACGGGAAAGGAGUUUAGCUCAGGCAUCCCUCCCUUCCACUGGCCUCCAGGCCAGCCUAGAUGCAGGUCCUAAGCAGACUGGGGCCUGGCUCCUGCCACCCCACACCCUGACCCCUUUGGGGCAUAUGCUCAUUGUUGUGGCAGGUGGUACCUUCAGAAGGAUGAGAUGAGGGUCAUGUUUUCCUCCACUCUUGCCAGGCCUGGUCCCCAGUUCUCACCAGCUGAUGGCCUCCUCCUUCUGAAGGGGCAGGCUCCUGUCUCCUGAGGUCUCUCCAGGCCAUUACCUUGCUAACUGCUAAGUGAGGUAGGAGAGGAGAGUGCUGCUCCUCAUCUAGACUGCUGGAGAGCCAACUUCUUUAUGGGUCAGGGCCCCCUCUCUUGACCAUCGACCACCUGGACAAAUUAAUCAGAACUACGGAUGUGAAGAGGGAGUGGCAUUAAAGUAAUGAAGCAAAGAUAGGAAGCUGGGGCUUAUGUUGAUUUAAUUUUCACAAAGAUCAGAUUGGAUGCCCUCUGAUGUGGGGCUGUGGAGACAACCUGACAGAUCUGGGAUGGAGGCAGGUAUAGCAGCAUUGGGUUUUGGUAUCACCAUCACCUGUAAUACCAACUAAUCUCCAAAUAAAACCCAAACUCUGUACCUUAA